AUUUUAUCUAACCUAAAAUAUUUAAAAUACCAUUUUUCAUGUGGAAAUAUUUUACAUUUUUUCAUGUUGAAUCCUCAAAAUAAAGUAUUUCAUACUUACAGCACGUCUCAGUUUAGGCUAGCCACAUUUCAAGUGCUCAUUGGCCACCCCUUGCUGAGUGGCUACUGUCUUGACAGUGUUAAGAGUGAUUUUCAUGAAAGUAGAUGCAAAGCUUUCAGAGACACAGCAUGGUAUACUGGUUUUGAGUUGGAUCCAGAUUCAAAUUCUAGCUUUGGCUGUAGUGCUGCAUUUAUUUAUUCUUAAAAUAUUUACUGACAUCUGUUCUCAAAAAAUCAUAGUCUGUUUCUACAUAGGGUCAGUCGUAUGAAUACUGGAGAGAAGUAUCAUGUUUUAUUGUGCUAAUUAUUGCAAGACCCAAGGAAGGGAGUGGUCAGUUCUAUCUGGGAAAGAGUUGGUAGUGGUCAGGAAGGGCUUUGCAAAGAGGAGAGGCCUGAGCUCCAUCUUGGAAGAGGAGGUAGAUGAGGACAGAGGCAUUCUAGGAGGAGGCAGGAGCAAGGGCAGGGAGGCUUGCAACAGCACUGCCCAGGAGAUUGCUUAUAGCUUGGUUCACAUGGAGCAGGAAUGGGUGGUUGAAAGGGUGGUGUGGCUGAGCUGGAGCUGAGGGCCAUGUUAUUUGAGGGCACCUACAAGGGGCUUUAGAAUGCAUUUCAUAUUAGGCAGUGGACACCCACAGAAGAGCUUCAAGAAGUAAGUGAUGAGGUGGGAUUUGAUCUUUCUUGUGUUGUUACCUUGGGCAAGUUAUUGACCUUUCAGAUCUGCCCCCCUUAGUCUCCUAUUCUGCAACAUUGGGUGAUUGAAAUCUACUCAGGCUGUUGCUAUGAGGAUUAAGUGAACUAGUAUGUGAAGCAUACCUGAUGGUCCAGCUCAGACUCCUGCUGAAUCGAGAGACCGCUUCUCUGGUAGUGUCCAUCUGUUGCCCUAGCUCCUGUUCUUCAUUGUAGUUGUGCUCCAGCAGUACCCAGGGAAAGCUUUCAAGAAUAUAAAUUGUUGGAGCACAACAAUCAGCCUCAGGGUGGUGUCCAGGAAUCUAUGUUUAACAAAUCUAUGUUUAACAAAUUCUCUUUGUGGUUAUUAUGCAGCCACCUGUUUCGGGUUUGCAUACCAAUGUGCAGAGUUCACGUCCUCAACUCUUAUCUAGGAUUCUGGGCCAUUCGGUAACAUCAGCUCUUCCUACCUCUUACAUCAGCUUCCGUGUACUGUUUCCUGGCCGGUGGUCUGUAGACCCUAGUCUGAUCACAGUUGGUAAUUACCAGUGGCCUAGGGCUACUCUGUUUGAGGUUGACCAGUUGGUUCUUAGGUGGCUCUUCAUAGAUUGGCCUCAUUGAAAUGGUACCUGACAUCUUCUACACAUGUAUAUAUCUACUUCACAGACUUUAGCCAGUACUCCUUAAUUUUGUUCACACUCUUAUUUAAUAUCUGUAUUAACAUAAAGUCACGUUCUAACUCCUUUCCACAAUGUGAAGUAUAAUUCCAACUUGUCUGUUAAUUCAGAGCUGUUCUAUUUGCAGCUCUUUAUCUAUGACCAUACCCAUUAUAAUAAUAAUGACAAUUUUCUUUUUUUUUCUGUUACAAUUAGUACUAUCACUGCCAUCAUUGGUACAUUUACCUUCAACCCUGUAGUGGUCCACAGUAGAUCCAAAUAUCUCUGUUUAAAGGGGAAAGUCGCUAUUGGAACAACACAGAGUGCCUCUGAAUGUCAGAUUUACUUUGCUUGCAUUUCAUUUCAUGGUCUUAUGUGUUUUUAAGAUUCUGAUUGGAUGUGAACAAAAUGACAGGUUUCAUCUAGCAUGUCAACUUUGACUUCGUCACCACCAUUCUGUGACCAUGUCACAGAAUGCUGAUUUUAAUCUUACAUCUUAUCCUCACAUAAUUAAUCUAAAAAAUAGGGAAAGAGAAAUGGGUGGCACUAAAAGGAGAUUAAAAAGUUUAUUUUGCAGCUGGCUGCUCUUUCAUGCAAAAACAAAACAAUUUAUAGUAGGCUGCUGAUUUAAUGGGUCUCCUAGUGGGAGGGAAAAUUAUUUAAACCCUUUGUUAUUCCUUCUCAGAAGAAAAUGCACUUUGGGAACUUGUGAAUUUUCUAUAUCUGGGGUACCCAAAUGGCCUUGAUUCCACUAGCUUUUACUUCCAUUAGUGUUGUGCAUGCUUCGAAUUAACAUUGUGUUGGGGUGGUUGUGAUGCUGUUGUGCUGGUGGUGGUAGUUGUGGUAGGUCCUAAAAUAGAUGGGUUACUACAUUUAUUACAAGACAGAAGUAAAUGUUCCCUUCAUUGCCCCAUGGACUUGGGCUUGGACCUGUGUGGGAUGCUGCUCCCUGGCCAUGCCUGUCCUGAGCUAGUGGGCAGCUCUUCCCCACGCUUCCCUCUGCAUCUUAUUCCUGCAUCCAUCUGCCCCCUGCAUCUUGUCCCUCGCUUGCUCUUGCCUGCUUUCCCUUUCACCUGCCCCUGUUAGAGAUCAGCAUGCUCCCUCUCACCUUUUUGUCUUCCAGCCCUCAGCUUUUCUUUCUGUCAUAUCUAUGCUCUUGGAAAAGAGUCUUAUGUUGCAAGGGGGAAGCCGAGGGGGUUGGAAGUAAUUGGGGACUGGGUGGGAAGAAAGAAUUGAAAAGAUACACAUAAGCCCUUCCAAAUGCUGGAGCUAAUUCCUUUCCUUUCUUAUCUUUUAGAUACCAUUGAUGGUAAGUUAGAAUGGAAUCAGUUACUCAUACCCAAACCAUUGUUGCUCAGAAAAAUGAUGUAUGUUGAGCAAUAGGUAGUUUAGAAAAUGUAAUUGUUUCAUAAUCACUGGGGUUUUCAAUCCUGAUUUUUUUUUUUGUUUGGAAAAAUUAUGAAAUUGCGAUAUGUGUAGGUAAAAAAAUGGUUGAGUAUCAGCAAUUUUGUAUAAGUCAACCUAAUAAUAGCAGGCAUUCUGUGGUGUCUAUGCCUCCACAUUUGGGAGGAAAAUUUGUCUCUUUUCUACCACUAGCAACUAAUCUUCCUGUUGGACAAUUUAGAGAAGAGAGUAAUUUGCUGAUUUUUUGAAUUGAAAUUUUCUUAACGAUUUAAUUAAUAUUAAUGUUGUUAAUACUGUAGGAUUCAUAGCUACUCUGGUUUUUUAUUGCUUCUGAAUUAGAAGAAAAUAAGCAUGACAGUAUAAAUUUGGUACACAAUAUGAAAAUUAAGAUCUACAAAAUGGACGUGAUUAUUCAUAUAUCAGAGGUAUUCUUCCCCUGACAAAAGCUCUGUCUUAAGUCCUUAAGAUACUUCAUUUAUAUGGUUUAUUUAAGAAUCAGUUUUCAGAUCAUUAACUACUUGAGGGAUUAAUAUAGAAAGAAAACUGAAGUCAUGUAAUCCACUGAGGAUUAAUCUGAAAAUAAGAUUAAGUAUCUCUAAAAUCCUAGACUCAGCUAAUGGAAAAAAUGGUGAGUUGAUGAAGCAACUCCAAUUAUGAAGAGUUUGUGGUAUAAUUGUUGCAUAGAUUCAGGGACUUCUGAACUAACUUUAUGUUUUGGUGAGAAGACCUAUUAUAAUAAAAUUACUGUUAAUGCUUUCCUGAAUCUUUCUCCUUCUAAAUUUUCCUGUAUCUUUUUCUUUUUAAGGUUUCCACAGCUGGAUUGUUUACUAGGGCCAAUUGUCACCAAUGGCAGUAAAACUCAUUUUCUGGGGAAUAGGGUCUCAUGGACUGAUUGGCUCUCAUUCAGCAGGAACCUAACAGAUAAGUCUUCCUGCUGUAUAUCAAGACAAUGCUUGGUUUUCAAGCUGUUCUGAGAAUGAUUAAAGCAGUGUCGCAAGGUGACAUUGUCAGGGGAGAACAAGCAGCUUGAGAAUUUCCUCUUAAUCUGAUUGCAGCUUGAAGGCAGCCCAUUUCCAUUAAGUAGGACUGCAUGGCAAGCAGCCCCACCAAAGGGUUGACAAUGAGCGUCCCAGUGGCUCCUAAGAAAUCAUGUUACACUCAGUUGCGGGACAACAGAAAUGCAGCAAGAAAUAAUAAUGAAAGCAUCUUAAGUCUGGGAGAUACGAAUGCCAAUCAAAUCAUGUUGGAGGUCAGCUCCUCUCAUGACGAGUCCAAGACAUGUGACCUGGGAGAUGAAAUUGGAAAUACAAAUUCAAGUGAGCCAGAAAACCGUACCCAUUUCCAUAAGGAAUUUCACCAACUUCAGGGCUUUGGGAAAGGCUCUCAGGCUGGCUCUGCCAGCCUGAAAGAUUUUAGACUUUCUUCAACCAUUCAGAGGGAACUCAAUGAAGAGCACACAGUGGAGAGAGGCACAGAUAGCCUGCAGACCACGCGGAGUAUUCAGGGACCAAGUCUGUCGAGUUGGAGGAAUGUGAUGAGUGAGGCCAGUCUAGACGUUUUGGCUAAAAGGGAUGCUGAAAUUCCCCGGCAUGUUCCCAAGGAUAAACUGGCAAAGACCCUUGACAAUGAGGAACUGAGGAGGCAUUCUUUGGAAAGAGCAAGCAGCUCUGUAGCUGCAGUCGGGAGCCUGACUCCGCAGCAUCCACAGCCUCUAUCCCUCGACUCCCGGGAAGCACGGGGUCAGAUACCUGGGGGUGGGGAGGGGCCACAGAAGACAUUGCCAGACCACGCUGUCCCGGCAGCUUUCCCUGCAACUGACAGUACCUCAGAGGGAAAGAGUGUGCGUCAUCCUAAACCAUCUACCUCAGAAAGCAAGCAGAGCACUCCCUCAGAGACCCAAACAGUGGGGGCACAUGUACUGCAGGUGUGCAGUGAGCACACAUCACAUUCCGCCCAUCCAGAGCCUGCUCUGAAUUUGACUUUGGCAUCGAAGGAAAUCCCAAGUAAACUGGAAGCACAAUUAGGUCAGGGAAAGGGAGAGGCCAAGCUGGAUCUGAAAUAUGUUCCUCCCAGGAGAGUUGAACAGGAGGGAAAGGCAGCCCAGGAAGGGUAUCUGGGAUGCCACAAGGAAGAGAAUCUGUCAGCCUUGGAGGGAAGGGAUCCAUGUGGGGAAGCACACCCGGAAGCCACCGAUGCACUUGGCCAUCUGCUGAACAGUGACCUCCACCACCUUGGGGUGGGAAGAGGCAACUGUGAAGAGAAGAGAGGAGUCAACCCAGGGGAGCAGGAUUCUCUCCACACCACCCCCAAACAGGGCUCUGCUUCCUUAGGAGGGGCUGAUAAUCAGCCCACUGGCAAAAUUUCACCAUGUGCAGGUGAGAAGUUGGGUGAAAGGACAUCCAGCAGCUUUUCACCAGGUGACAGUCAUGUGGCUUUUAUUCCUAAUAAUCUGACUGACAGCAAGCCCUUGGAUGUCAUUGAGGAGGAAAGGCGGUUGGGCAGUGGGAAUAAGGACAGUGUUAUGGUUUUGGUGUUCAAUCCUUCUGUUGGAGAGAACAAGACGGAGGUGCCUGAGCCCCUGGACCCUCAAAGUGGCCGCUCAGAAGCACGGGAAAGCAAAGAGGUCACCACAUCUGUUGCUGAAAACAGGAACCUUCUAGAGAAUGCAGAUAAGAUUGAAAGCACCUCAGCAAGAGCAGAUUCAGUUCUCAAUAUUCCAGCACCCCUCCACCCAGAGACAACUGUGAACAUGACCUACCAGCCUACAACACCCAGUAGCAGUUUUCAGGAUGUUAGCGUGUUCGGUAUGGAUGCGGGGUCCCCCUUGGUAGUUCCACCCCCUACUGAUAGUGCACGCUUGUUGAACACGUCCCCCAAAGUGCCUGACAAGAACACUUGCCCCAGUGGGAUCCCCAAGCCUGUCUUCACACAUUCCAAGGACACACCUUCCUCGCAGGAGGGAAUGGAGAACUAUCAGGUUGAAAAAACAGAGGAGAGGACAGAAACUAAGCCCAUCAUUAUGCCCAAGCCCAAGCAUGUGAGGCCCAAGAUCAUCACCUACAUCAGGAGGAAUCCCCAGGCCCUGGGCCAGGUGGACGCCUCGCUGGUUCCAGUGGGGCUUCCAUAUGCCCCGCCCACAUGUACCAUGCCUCUUCCCCACGAAGAGAAGGCAGCAGGUGGUGACCUGAAGCCAUCUGCCAACCUCUAUGAGAAAUUCAAGCCAGACCUGCAGAAGCCAAGGGUCUUCAGUUCCGGAUUGAUGGUGUCUGGAAUCAAGCCCCCGGGACAUCCUUUCAGUCAAAUGAGUGAAAAGUUUUUGCAGGAGGUUACAGACCACCCUGGAAAAGAAGAGUUUUGUUCUCCUCCCUAUGCUCAUUAUGAAGUCCCUCCAACUUUCUAUCGGUCAGCCAUGCUCCUUAAGCCCCAGCUAGGAUUGGGUGCAAUGUCCCGUUUACCAUCUGCAAAGAGCAGGAUUCUGAUUGCAAGUCAGAGGUCUUCAGCGAGCGCCAUCCACCCACCAGGACCCAUAACAACAGCCACCAGUCUCUACAGUUCCGAUCCUUCAGGUGUGCAUGCUCUCAGUGGGACAUGGUUUAACUACAGUGGUUCCCUUGGAGAUCUUUCAGCAGAUUUAAAGAAAGCUUCCAGUUCAAAUGCUGCAAAAUCCAAUCUCCCGAAAUCUGGUCUCCGUCCUCCCGGAUACUCACGUCUCCCGGCAGCCAAACUGGCGGCAUUUGGCUUUGUCCGGAGCUCCAGCGUCUCCUCAGUCUCCAGCACCCAGUCCGGGGACAGUGCACAGCCAGAGCAGGGCCGGCCAGCCACCCGUUCAACCUUUGGGAAUGAAGAACAGCCAGUUCUGAAGGCAUCUCUGCCUUCUAAGGACACACCCAAGGGGGCCGGCCGGGUGGCCCCUCCAGCAUCCUCCAGUGUGACAGCACCCCGCAGGAGUUUACUUCCAGCGCCAAAAUCCACUUCCACACCCGCUGGAACAAAGAAAGAUGCUCAGAAAGAUCAAGAUACGAAUAAACCUGCUGUUUCAUCUCCUAAGAGAGUAGCAGCUUCAACCACCAAGCUUCAUUCACCAGGAUACCCAAAGCAGAGGACUGCGGCAGCUCGAAAUGGGUUUCCGCCCAAGCCGGACCCGCAGGCCCGUGAGGCUGAGCGGCAGCUGGUGCUGCGGCUGAAGGAGCGGUGUGAGCAGCAGACCAGACAGCUGGGCGUUGCGCAAGGGGAGCUGAAGAGGGCCAUCUGCGGCUUUGAUGCCCUCGCCGUGGCCACGCAGCAUUUCUUUAGAAAGAUCCAUAUGUAUGUUAUCAUCAAUAGAAGCUCCUCAGAAUGACCAUUACUUAUAUGAAGACCCAACACACAAACUAAGCAAGGGAUCCGAAAGAUCUCAGUUGAGUUCCAGUUCAGGGUAAGAGGGAGGAAGCACACUCCACCCUUCUUCUCCCACUAAAUUCAGCUACAAACAACUGGACCAAAUGCAUCAAGCAGCUAUUUGAGAACUUAAAAGGAUAUGCAGUGGGCAGAUUAGAAAGAAGAGUUGAAUUGAAAGUAUCAUAAAAUUAGUGGUGAACAUACAAGUUUUUCUUUCCAGUAUUCUCUGACUUGAAGUCAGUUCAGCUUGAAACCUGGAAGUGGUCACCUGGACCUGGACAGAAAGAGCUCCAGGAGAAACUUUUUAGGUCUGACUCGAGAAGUGGGAAAGGGAACUCCUAGAACUCAGAGACAGCUAAUGAAGUCUCAUUUUUCUUCUUCAUUUCCCCAUACCCUAAUCUGUGUAGCCUUGCAGUGGUGGUAGCACCAACCUGCCAGAGGGAAACUGUAAGGGAAGGAAACUUUCCCAUUUGCUUGCAGGAGCUGUGGUCCCUGUUUUUAUUAUCUCCAUGUACACAUACCAUCUGUCCACAAACAGGAGUGCAGUUGUGAAAAGUGCAUAGAGCAGGGUAACUAAAGGCCCAGCUUUUUGGCUCGAGGACUAACAAGGGGGGCACCCAGGGAACUGGAAAGGAUAGCAGAUAUUGAGGCAAAGGAGGAACGUGGGAAAAUGACCCCUUAAAUUGUUUUUGAACCCCUGGGCUCACCCCUGAGCUGUAUGUGAAUCUCAUCCUAACAGCAUACACGGACUUUGAGAAUUGAACUACAGAGCAAACCAUCACCAGAGUGCUAGACUGGCCAUUGUGGGAGGCACAUGAGGUAUGGAUCCUAAUAGUACUUCAAAAGCUUUGAAAACGGAGCUAACUUUGGAAGCACAACUUACAGAAGGCUGGAUGGAACUGAUAACCUGAACUCUACCUCACUGACUGCCUGCUGCUGAUUAUUCAUUAGAUUUAAGCAAGGCCCAGAGGAGUCUUAUGAUGUAAUAUUCAAAAUGCUUAGAACACAAUUUAAAACUAUUUAGCAUACAAAGAAUCAGGAAAUCCUCAGCUUAUAUGGGAAAAGCUAAUCAACAAACAGUAAAACCAUGAUGACACAGAUGUUGCAUUUAUUUGACAAAAAAUGUUAAAAGUAGCUAUUGCAGAAUGCUUCAGGAAGUACAAGCAGUUACCCUUGAAAUUCUUCAAAGAAAGAUGUAUCAAAGGAAGAAAAGAUACACAGAAGAAACAAGUGGAAAUUUUAGAGCUAAAAAAUACAAUAACCAAAAUAACUGGAUGGAAAUGAUGGAGAAAAAAGUCAGUGAACUUGAAGAUAGAUCAGUAGAAAUUGUCCAAUCUGAACAACAGAAAGAAAAUAAUUUUUAAAGAACAGAGCCUCAGAAACCUAACAGACAAUUUUAAAAAGGUCUAAUAUUUUUGUAAUAGGCGUUCCAGAGAGAAGAAAGAAUGUGGUGCAGAGAAAAUAUGUGAAGAAAUAAUGGCUGAAAACUUCCCAAAUUUGUUGAAAGAAAUAAACCUACACAUUCAGGAAGCUCAGUGAACCACAAACAGGAUAAGCCCAAGGAAAUUCAUAUCUAGAUAUAUUCUAAUUAAACUGCUAAAAACUAAAGACAAAAAAUACUGUAAGCAGUCAAAGAAAAAUUACACAUUACCUAUCGGGGAACAACAAUUCAAAUGACUGCAGAUUUCUCAUCAUAAAUUAUGAAGGCCUGAAGACAGUGGCACAUUUUCAAAGUAGUGAAACAAACAUCAACCCACAAUUCUAUAUCCAGUGAAAAUAUACUUUAUAAAUGAAGAUGAAAUAGGCCGGGCAUGGAGGCUCACGCCUGUAAUCCCAGCACUUUGGGAGGCCAAGGUGGGUGGAUCACCUGAGGUCAGGAGUUCGAGACCAGCCUGGCCAACACAGGAAACCCCAUGUCUACUAAAAAUACAAAAAUUAGCCAGGUGUGGUGGCACACACCUGUAAUCCCAGCUACUCGGGAGGCUGACCUGUAAUCCCAGCUACUCGGGAGGCUGAGACAGGAGAAUCACUUGAACCUGGGAGGAGGAGGUUGCAGUGAGCCGAGAUCAUGCCAUUGCACUCCAGCCUGGGUGACAAGAGUGAAACUCUGUCUCAAAAAAAAUAAAAUAAGAAGAUGAAAUAAAGACAUUCUCACAUAAAGAAAAGCUAAAAGAAUUCACUGUCUGCAACCCUGAUCUAAAAGAACUGUUAAAGAAAUUGCUAAGAUAUGGAACCAACCUAAAUGCUUAUCACCUGAUGAGUGGAUAAAGAAAAUGUGGUUUUAGAUUGGUGCAAAAGUAAUCGUGGUUUUUGCCAUUACUUUUAAUAAGAAACUCACUGGGUGGAAAUGACAGAGAAAAAAGUCAGUGAACUUGAAGAUAGAGCAGUAGAAACUGUCCAAUCUGAACAACAGAAAGAAAAUAAUUUUUAAAGAACAGAGCCUCAGGA